AGUUUGGCUGUUCAGGAGAGUCAGGCCAAUGGGGCCGCAGUUCUUUCUUUUUUUUUUCUUUAUUCUUAUUUUUGGAGACAGGGUCUCGCUCUGUUGCCCAGGCUGGAGUGCGGUGGUGCGAUCACGGUUCCAUGCAGCCCCCGACCUCCCGGGCUCAGGUGAUUCUCCCGCCUCAGCACCGCGAGCAGCUAGGACCACAGGCGCGAGCCACUGCGUCCGGCCGGCGGGACUUAUUUGUCAGGCGGGGAUUGGGUUCCGCCAGCCUAAAGGGAGGGGUAAGCGCCAGAAUAUGAAUCGCCGGGAAGCUGGGAGAAAGCUCCGGGAAACCCUGAGCAGCCAGGUCGCCUGCUCCGCCCGCUCCCGCUCCCGAUCUCUGAUUGCUCCUAACUGACGUCACUCCCGGUCUGUCCCCGCCCACUCGGUGCUGCCAUUGGCAGUCGGUCGUGGGUACGCGGCUCCUGUGGGGGAGGGGGGAGCUAUGGGAGGGGGCGGGAAUUCCCGACUCUAGGCCGGAAGCGCGCGGAGACCAUGUAGUGAGACCCUCGCGAGGUCUGAGAGUCACUGGAGCUACCAGAAGCAUCAUGGGGCCCUGGGGAGAGCCAGAGCUCCUGGUGUGGCGCCCCGAGGCGGUAGCUUCAGAGCCUCCAGUGCCUGUGGGGCUGGAGGUGAAGUUGGGGGCCCUGGUGCUGCUGCUGGUGCUCACCCUCCUCUGCAGCCUGGUGCCCAUCUGUGUGCUGCGCCGGCCAGGAGCUAACCAUGAAGGCUCAGCUUCCCGCCAGAAAGCCCUGAGCCUAGUAAGCUGUUUCGCGGGGGGCGUCUUUUUGGCCACUUGUCUCCUGGACCUGCUGCCUGACUACCUGGCUGCCAUAGAUGAGGCCCUGGCAGCCUUGCACGUGACGCUCCAGUUCCCACUGCAAGAGUUCAUCCUGGCCAUGGGCUUCUUCCUGGUCCUGGUGAUGGAGCAGAUCACACUGGCUUACAAGGAGCAGUCAGGGCCGUCACCUCUGGAGGAAACAAGGGCUCUGCUGGGAACAGUGAAUGGUGGGCCGCAGCAUUGGCAUGAUGGGCCAGGGGUCCCACAGGCGAGUGGAGCCCCAGCAACCCCCUCAGCCUUGCGUGCCUGUGUACUGGUGUUCUCCCUGGCCCUCCACUCCGUGUUCGAGGGGCUGGCGGUAGGGCUGCAGCGAGACCGGGCUCGGGCCAUGGAGCUGUGCCUGGCUUUGCUGCUCCACAAGGGCAUCCUGGCUGUCAGCCUGUCCCUGCGGCUGUUGCAGAGCCACCUUAGGGCACAGGUGGUGGCUGGCUGUGGGAUCCUCUUCUCAUGCAUGACACCUCUAGGCAUCGGGCUGGGUGCAGCUCUGGCAGAGUCGGCAGGACCUCUGCACCAGCUGGCCCAGUCUGUGCUAGAGGGCAUGGCAGCUGGCACCUUUCUCUAUAUCACCUUUCUGGAAAUCCUGCCCCAGGAGCUGGCCAGUUCUGAGCAAAGGAUCCUCAAGGUCAUUCUGCUCCUAGCAGGCUUUGCCCUGCUCACUGGCCUGCUCUUCAUCCAAAUCUAGGGGGCUUCAAGAGAGGGGCAGGGGAGAUUGAUGAUCAGGUGCCCCUGUUCUCCCUUCCCUCCCCCAGUUGUGGGGAAUAGGAAGGAAAGGGGAAGGGAAAUACUGAGGACCAAAAAGUUCUCUGGGAGCUAAAGAUAGAGCCUUUGGGGCUAUCUGACUAAUGAGAGGGAAGUGGGCAGACAAGAGGCUGGCCCCAGUCCCAAGGAACAAGAGAUGGUCAAGUCGCUAGAGACAUAUCAGGGGACAUUAGGAUUGGGGAAGACACUUGACUGCUAGAAUCAGAGGUUGGACACUAUACAUAAGGACAGGCUCACAUGGGAGGCUGGAGGUGGGUACCCAGCUGCUGUGGAACGGGUAUGGACAGGUCAUAAACCUAGAGUCAGUGUCCUGUUGGUCCUAGCCCAUUUCAGCACCCUGCCACUUGGAGUGGACCCCUCCUACUCUUCUUAGCGCCUACCCUCAUACCUAUCUCCCUCCUCCCAUCUCCUAGGGGACUGGCGCCAAAUGGUCUCUCCCUGCCAAUUUUGGUAUCUUCUCUGGCCUCUCCAGUCCUGCUUACUCCUCUAUUUUUAAAGUGCCAAACAAAUCCCCUUCCUCUUUCUCAAAGCACAGUAAUGUGGCACUGAGCCCUACCCAGCACCUCAGUGAAGGGGGCCUGCUUGCUCUUUAUUUUGGUCCCGGAUCCUGGGGUGGGGCAGAAAUAUUUUCUGGGCUGGGGUAGGAGGAAGGUUGUUGCAGCCAUCUACUGCUGCUGUACCCUAGGAAUAUGGGGACAUGGACAUGGUGUCCCAUGCCCAGAUGAUAAACACUGAGCUGCCAAAACAUUUUUUUAAAUACACCCGAGGAGCCCAAGGGGGAAGGGCAAUGCCUACCCCCAGCGUUAUUUUUGGGGAGGGAGGGCUGUGCAUAGGGACAUAUUCUUUAGAAUCUAUUUUAUUAACUGACCUGUUUUGGGACCUGUUACCCAAAUAAAAGAUGUUUCUAGACA